GCCCAGGCUGGAGUGCAGUGGCCUGAUCUCGGCUCACUGCAACCUCCGCCUCCUGGGUUCAAGCGAUUCUCCUGCCUCAGCUUCCCAAGUAGCUGGGACUACAGGCGCGCACCACCAUGCCCAGCUAAUUUUGUAUUUCUAGUAGAAAUGGGGUUUCACCAUGUUGGCCAGGCUGGUCUUGAACUCCUGACCUCAGGUGAUCCACCCAACUUGAUGCCUCCUCUUCCAAACUCUCACUCAGAAGCAGUGCUGUCCUAA